AGUCUUAGACGACUGCGUCGUGCUAUGACCGGACUUUUUCUUGAAAGGGGAUGACAGCAUGGGAGGCAAUGGCUCCACAUGUAAACCCGACACUGAAAGACAAGGCACUCUCUCCACAGCAGCCCCAACAACUAGCCCUGCACCCUGUCUCUCUAACCACCACAACAAAAAACAUUUAAUCCUUGCCUUUUGUGCUGGGGUUCUACUGACACUGCUGCUGAUAGCCUUUAUCUUCCUCAUCAUAAAGAGCUACAGAAAAUAUCGAAGGGAGAGGCUUCCCAUUUCCCCAGGCCCAUUGCUGAGAUGGGUCCCUCUUCUUUCUGGCACCAUGGCAGAUCACUCCAAGCCCCAGGCCCCAGAUCCUCACUCAGAUCCUCCAGCCAAGCUUUCAUCCAUCCCAGGGGAAUCACUUACCUAUGCCAGCACAACUUUCAAACUCUCAGAAGAAAAGAGCAAUCACUUGGCUGAGAACCAUUCUGCAGACUUUGACCCCAUUGUCUAUGCUCAAAUUAAAGUAACAAACUAACUCAGCUUUUCCAAUGAGGCUUGAAUCCAUUUCCUCUCAUCUCAGCCCUAUCUUCACACAUCACUUUCACUUUUUUACAAAUUUUGGACCACCACCUGUGUGAAACUGCAGUCGGAGUUGUUUAGAUGUGAUCUGGCAAUGCUAUCCAGCAUCUUUGGAGACCAAUGGUCAGUCUUUUCCUGGCCAGAGGAAAGAUUGAUGGCCCUCCCACUUGAACUGACAGCCUGUGAGCCCCUUGGGGGCAUAGACUGCCUUCCUUGGACCCUUCCAAAGUGUGUGGUACAGAGCUCAGUGCACAGAGUAUUCACCCAGCAUCAUGAAUCAACUUGGGAGGAGUCAACCAAAUGAACAAUCUACCAAAAAUUUCAAAUAAAGUCAAACCCCCCACA